UGUUUAUUUAGCUCAGGGUUCUGCAGCCUGGGAAGUUCAAGAGCAUGGCCCUGGCUUCCGGGGAGGGCCGUCCUGUGGGGUGAUAACAUGGUGAAAAAGGCCAAAGAGGAAGUGAAUAUGUGUGAAGAGCCAGGACCAAACAAGAGAGUAACCUCACUUUAUAACAGCCCACUCUCUCAGGAACUGAUCCAUUUCCAUGGAAAUUAAUCCAGGCCCUCAAGAGGGAGAACUCACUCACUACCACAAGCAUGGCAGCAAACCAUUCGUGAGGGAUCUGCUCCCGUGACCCAACACCUCCUGCUAGGCCCCACCUCCCAACAUCACCACACUGGAAAUCAAAUUUCAUCAUGAGUUUCAGUGGGGACAGAAAGACCAUACCCAAACUAUAGCACUCUCUGUUUAUUUUUAAUCUUUAUUGUUCCAAGUGAGACCCUUAAUGCUCUUUCCGUGAACUAAAGAGCAUUCAAGAAAUUGCUUUUGGAUUUAUCUCCCGAAAAUACACUCAGGCCACAUCUCAUUGAGGGGAUGCUCAGCUCUCCCCAGUGACAUCUAUAAAUUAGGACCUGUCUAGGUUUUCACCUUGGUAAUCAGUGGCCCCUACAUAUAUCCCUAGCCCUUCUUUAUUGCUCAGUCUCCCCAGCAAUAACCUCAUACCUCCAUAUAACCCCAAUUCCAGCCCAACUGGAUAUUACGAUUACCCAAAUGCCCCCUUGGCUGUCUGAAUUUCAUGCAUUGGAAGCAUUUCCUUCCUUCAAGUCCUAUUUGAAGGACUGCUUCUCACUGAGUACUUUCUCAGUCUCUUAACUGUCUGUAUCCUCUCCUCUCCUUGGACUCUAGUAGCAUUUUCCAUGGAUCUGAUGUCUCUUAAUGUACUUUAACACGUAUCAUAUCAUCAUUGUUGUUAACAUCAUCAUAACGUGGCUUCUCGGGUGAUGUCUAUGUACUGGGUACUGUGUGAAUCUCUUAUUAUAUGUUAUCUUUUUUUUUUUUUUGUAUAAACUCAUUGAGGUAUAUAUUAUAUUUGAGACUCAUUAGCUUGCCUAAAUUUCCAGAGCUAGAGGCAAACAUCUCAAUCCAUUCUGAGUGUCAUUAUAGCCUUGGAAUUAAGAUGCCCUACCUGAUACCAGACUCUCUGGGUUCAAAUCCAGGUUGUCUUCCUUACCAGCUCUGUAACUCUUGGGCAAGCCACUUGACCUUUCUAUCUGUAGUUUCCACAAUUAUCAAAUGAAGAUGAUCAUUAUAGUGCUUACCUCACUUAGCCAUCAAGAGCAUAGUAAGUGCUUGAUAAUCUUGUCUGUUAUCUAUCUUGUCUGGCCCACAUUCAUGCCUUUGCCUGUGGCUUGAGCCACUUGUAUACUUCCCUAAUCCCAGAAGAACCAACAUAGUCAUGAGCCCUGAGGCUGAGAGCUCACUCUUCUGAUUUUCUUCAGUGUCCAGAAUAAUGGUUUGCACAGAGCAAGUGCUCAUUUAGUACUUGCAUUGAAUUCACUGAAUGCCCCUAGUUAUUUGAAAUAGGGCUACAAAUGGAUUGUUCCCAGGACUGGAAUUUCAGAGAAGCUACCUUGGGCUUACUCGUGACCCAACAUGUGUCAGUGUCUCCCCAGACUGACGGUGUGAAUAAAAAGUGCUUUCGGCUUGUAAAUAUCAACAUUAUAAAGACACCUCUAAAUAAACAUUUGACAUAGUAGCUUCCAUAAAUUGCCAAAUCUUUUUCUAAGGGUUGCCCCCCUUUUCUUACCGGAUUCUAUUUCAUAGUCUGGUUCAAGUCUCCCUAGAUUUUCCUCUUCUAAAAUAGAAACAACUGCUGAGCACGGUGAGAUGCGCCUGUAGUCCUAGCUACUCGGGAGGCUGAGGCAGGAAGAUUGCUUGAGCUCAGGAGUUUGGGACUAGCCUGGGCAACACAGCAAGACCCAGUCUCUUAAAAGAAAGAAAGGAAGAAAGAAACAACAGACGACAUAAUACCUUCAGAUGAAGGUACAAUACCAAGAAACUCAUACGUAAUAUUGUGAUUUAGAAAAUCAUGCUGUGGAAUUAUCAGUCCGCCUUUGGAAGUAGACCAGAUUCAGUGAAAAGGGCUGAUGAGGUCUGUGAGUUUGCUAGGAAAUCCAGGUCAAGCCACGUCCCCUGGUGCUGACAUGAAUGCAUCCUGUCUCCACAUCCUGUUUGUGGCGGGGCUGUGGUGUAGGGUGGAGACACCCAUGUUUUCCCCCAGGGAGCAUGUGUGUGUGCCCUGCGCCUGGGGCCUGUGUGUAUGGGAGUGAGGAUGUCACACAGAGGCAUGCCCUUCAGAGUGGGUCACAGGGCGCUUCUGCCCCACGGAGGUGGAUGUGUCCUUCUGUGCCCAGCAUCUUCUCGGUCCCCAUGAGCUGUUAGAGCAUCCCUAAGAUAACCAAAGGCAACUGGAGCCAUCAUUAUUUGUUUUUUCAGGCACACUAGGGUGGGAAGCAUAGGCAAAAUGGCAAACUUAAUUUUCAGAAAAUAAAUGGACUGGCCCAAGAGCCAGGUGUUGUUAUGAUAUUAGGUACUCUUCUGCCUUAAUCAGUAGAGGCUGAGGGCAUGAGGGCCAGGUCACUGGCCAGGAGGCUCGUCCAUCUGUGACUUGUCCUCUUUGCCACUUCAUCUUCUGGGCUUCAGCUCCCUCGUGGGCAUGGUGAGGAGUGUGAGUCAGGUGGUCUCCAGGGUCCUUCUAGCUCAGGCCAUCUUUUGUUUUCUGCUCCAGUCUAAAGCAUGCCCUGCACCGAUCAAUUUAGCUUGGACUCUGCAUAUCCCACUAUGUUGUAGCUGGCCUAGGCUCUGGAGCUGGACAGAAUCUGAGCGUGAGUUUACGCUCCGCUAGUUGUGGGACUGGGAACAAGUUAUUCGAAUUCUUUACGCCUCAGGUUUCUAUUCAAUAAAGCAUGCACAAAAACAGCUCUUUUCAAGGGUGGUGCUGUGAAAUGCCCAGCACACUGCCUGGCACGCGAUAGGUGCUCACAUUCUGCUGUUCCCUCCCCUCACCCCCUCUGUAAUGUGCAGUGCUGCCCCUGGUGAGGGCAGUGAGUCUGUGGUGUCUCUUCUCAGGCUCAUUAGACGGUGCCAUACACACAGAGCUUAUCACUGGCCAUGGUCCCCUAAAAUAUGCCCUUCCCACAUGACCUUUCGUUUCUUUUGUGAUGCCUGCAAUGGGGGCGACUAGGAAACAACAGCUAUUUUCAUAGAGCCUGUGCAGUAGCAAUGCGCUGAAGCGUGCGUUUGUGCAGGCAUAACUGCGUCCACACGUGUGUGUGCACGCGUGCACCAUUGCACAGCAUAUUUGAAGGGCUCAGCAUUCCAGAAUGCAGGAGCUUGGGGUAGGAGCAGCUGGUCCACAAUCCUCCUCCUCAGCUGUUCCCAACUGGAAACUCCGUUGCCCUUCCCUCUGUCUGGCGAGUGAGCCACCAGCCGACCCGGACACAGCUUGAGUCCGCACGUCUGCCCUGUGUCCUUUGCCGGUGGCAGGCUGUGUGUGUUCUUGCUGGGAUGGCUGGGGACAGGUGCUGCUGCCAGGAAUUGUUUAAUGUACGGAGGUGGCUGCUGUUUAUUCUCUCUCCUGCAUAAGAAGAAACAGAAUAUUAGGCCAAGGAUGGGGUGAUGGUGGGAGGCUAUCAGUAAAUAAAUAUCAUUCCUAUACUUGCAGGAAGAUGUGGAGACUCAACACCUACAGCUUAGUGCGUGCUCCCUGCAUGUCUUAUUAAUUCUCCUACCAAAUCUAUAAUGCAGAUGGUAUUCUACAGUUAAGGAAACCAAGGUUUAGAAAGGUCAGUGACUUAGCAAGAUCACAGACCUUGGGUAAGGCAGAGCUGGAUUCUGAAUCCAGCUCUGUUUAUCUGCAAGGGGCAGACUGCUUCUCAUCCACCCAACUACAGGUACAAUCAAAGACUGGGGUGCUCGGAGAGACCAGUGAUGGGCCAGGCAGCUCAGGAAGUUUAAUUUGAUAAGCAUUUAUCCAGCAGUAAGCCCUGGAAAGAUGAGUAAGAUAGGUAGGGUAGCUGUCCUCUUACAAUCUGAAGACAUGGAAAGAUGCUUAUAAUGCAAUGCGAAAACCAUCAGGACAGGGGAACUGCAGAAGGAGGUAUGGUGAACCCCGCUUGGGGGAUAGGCAUGGUGCUGAGGGCCCUGUAUUUUGGCAUCAGUCAGGGUUCUAUUUGAGAAGUAGAAUGUUAAGAUAGAAUAAGGACUUGGUUAUAUGCUUUUGACCUCAUGCAUCACAGCCCGUGCUGGCUGCACAGGCCAGGUGAGGCUGUUCCUUCUGUGUCAGGUGGUACAGCCUGAAGUCAGCAGGGCAGGCAGUUCAGCAAAAACAAUGCCUGCAAAGUGAAGAGAGCAAGGACAAAGUCCACCCUGCCAGGGUGGGCUGACACCCAUGCCAUCAGUCACCGUCUCCAAGCGAGGCUUCAGCUUCGCGGGUGCAGAGGGCCUGCAGGAGUUGUUGACGUCCUUCCUCAGGAGCUCCACACAUCACAGGCCCAGGACUGAGGAGCUGAGGAGGAGACCCAGCAGGAAUGUGAGCGCUGUGGGCCCAGCUGCUGCCCCAUGCCAGCCCCUGACCCAGAGGACCAACAAUAACAGCUAUAGCAGGGCCCCAUGCCCACACUGACGGUGAAGCACGGAAAAAAAAGAGCUACUUUCUGCAUUUCAUGUAAAAUCUCUCUUGUGGUCCAGGCUAACCUGGAACUAUGCAAGGAAGAGAAUUCGGAGAAAUGUAAUCCGGCUGUUCUAAAUUGUCAAGACUCCAAAUCGUCACAGGUUCCCAUAGGAGUGAGAACCUGAGGGCUGACUGGGGGUUCUCUUAGGCAAAAGCAGAGAGGAAGGAAGUUCCUGGUGGAAGAAAGGGUGUGCGAAACCAUAGGAGCACAGCAUCUUGGGGGAAUGGGUGGUGGAGCCCCAGGCCUAGCUGGUGGAAGGCUUUCAGAGCCAGCUCAGGCAUUUCCUGGUGAUGGGCUUUGUAUUUUAGACGGGCCACUGUCAGCGUGAGGAGGUGGGCUGUGUGCAUCACAGGAGGCAGGGAGAACUGUGAAGAGAGGGAGAGAUCUGGAAGGUCUAAAGGCCUUGUCAAGCCUUUCUUUAUUUUGCUUCCACUUUCUAAAUUCUUUUAUCCACCGGCUGAUUCAUUACUUCGUUGAAUCUUUAGGGAGUGUCUCCUUCAUGUCAGGAAUGCUUGGUGGUCAAGACAACGCAGUCCCCAACCUCUCAUCUAAAAGCUUUGCCCAAAUAAAACCUUACAAGUCAGGAUAAUGCUUGAAAAGUAUUUGCCACUUGUUUUAUCGUAUUACUCUGUAUUCUUUUCUGAACACCUCACUUGCAGUAUUGCUUAUUUUAUUUUGGAGGUGUUGGAUACAAGGAGGGAAUGGAGAAUGAAGAUGGGCCCUGUGAUCCCUGGCCUCUCCUAGGCCAAGCCAGUGGUUGCAAGCAUAUCUGCACAUCACAAUUACUUGGAGAGCUUGUUGGAGAGACAGAUCCUCAGGCCUUGCCCAGACCUAAUGCAUUCAAUAUCCAGAUGUGGAACCCUGGAGGCUUCUAAGAAGUUUCCCAGGAGACUCUUAAGCAGCCAGCUUGGCUUUAUUCAUCGCCACCCAGAUCAGUGUCUUGUCAGCUUUAAGCUCUUGGCUUCUACUCUGCAUCGUAAGCACAGGUCGAGUUGGGGGCUGUUCAGCUGAUGUGGGUAGAGGUCAUUUCAUCGUCACGGUGACCUUGGAAAGCUUCCCGGUGUCUGAAUCAUUUCCAGCAGGUGCUGGUGCGCUCACAACAUCAGAAGGGGAAGGACGUGAAGUCAUCUGAGGGCAGGGUGAAAUCAGCGAGUGGAGUGAUUAAGAAUGGGAGGACAGGGUCCACUUGGAGUGAGUCUAGGUGUGGAGGGCGCAUGGAAGUGACAGAGAUGCUUGGGAAUUUAAAAAUGAGAUCUGAGAAGACAGGAAAACUUGAGUUUCCAUUUUCAUAGUAUUUAUAACAUAUACAAAUUUUCCAUUAGCCAUGUCUGUGAAUGAAUUAGAAGUGGGGCAGGGGAAGGCUGAAGUGGUUGCUGCUGGCUGGACGCAGAUUCAGGGCUGCCGCGUGUCCAUGCUGCCCGUUGGGAGAAGUAGGGCAGGUGGGCGGCUCCCACAGCCAUGGUCUGGAGGGGUUGUUGGUCACUGUGCUGUGGCAGCGAGAGGAAGGGCCCUCCAUGCCCGCAGUGCCUCCAGCCUUGGCCUUCAGUGCUGCUUCCCCUGGACUCCCCUGCUGCCCCCAGGGCAGCUGGCAGAAGAAAAGCGGCAGCCCCAGGCCCCACAUCCCUCCAGGGUCCUCUGUGUCCAGGCUGCACAACGGCCUGCGUGGCCAGCAGGCCUCGGGGAUGGUGAAUGGGAGCCACUGUUUGUUUCCACUGAGAAAGUCCUGACCUGCUUCCGGAGCCAUUGCCAUGGAAACGCAAGGAGGAGGUUCUUGAAUGGAGCCUCUUUCCUCCCCAUCUGCCCUACUCCCUUCCCCACCCCAGGCCGAGGCUGGUAAGGGCCAGCCCCCUGCUGCCUCACUUUCCCCCUAGGUUCUUGCACAUUUGGUAAAAAUACUCAAAGCUGGGGGCCCUCCCUGCCCGUCUCUAUAGGGAUCAGUGACCCCAUCUCCAUACCGCCCGAGCGUGUGGCAGCCCAUUCUCACAGCAGCUCUUAACCUGGGCCUGCCUCACGCAAACAGAGGGCCAGAGAGGGCCUUCCAGAGGAGCCCCUGCCAGCCUCAGCCACAUUUCCCCAUAGAAAAGCCUCUCUUGGACCCCAUAUUUAUUACACAUAUGCAGGAAAUUUUAAUAAAGGAAAUAGAGCAAACGAAUAAUUUUGCCCCAUUUACAAAAUACUUGGGAGCCAUUUAGUAAUGUAAAUAGCAGGCGCAGUGGCUCAUGCCUGUAAUCCAAGGACUUUGGGAGGCAGAGGCUGGUGGAUUGCUUGAGCCCAGGAGUUCGAGACCAGCCUGGGCAACAUGGCGAAAUCCUGUCUCUACAAAAACAAACAAAAAUUAGCUGGACAUGGUGGUGCGCGCCUGUAGUCCCAGCUAUUUGGGGGCUGAGGAGGUGGGAGGAUCACCUGAGCCUGGGGAGGUUGUGGCUGCAGUGAGCUAUAAUCACAUCACUUCAUUCCAGCCUGGCCAACAGAGUGAGACCCAGAGUGUCUCAUAACAAUAAUAAUAAUAAUAAUAAUAAUAAUAUAAUGUAAACAAAGGUACUUUCUUUUUAGUAGGCUGCUUAAGCUCAUAAGAAAUUUUUGCUCAUUUUUAUAAUAACUAGUUUUUGUGGUGAAAACAAUGUGCUACAGCCCUGUUUUAUUUUAUUUUGCUUUUGAUAAUAAUUUAGUAAUUCCUUAAGACAAAAAAAAAAAAAACCUAAGUAAAAUUUAAAAUUCACAGUGAGGCCAUAAAAUGAAGGCAUUUGUUUUUACUGGUUAGAUCAAAACCAGAAUAAAAAGCAGAAUUUCAAGGCCCCCUCCCCCGCCCCUUUUUUUUACACCUUAAUUUUUAUGCCUACUGAAGAAUCAUCAAAAGUCAGAAUUUGACCUGAAGCCGCAGACUCCAGGGGCAGCAUUACAAACUUAAAUUGCACUUUCAGUACCGGUAAUUAGAGACAAUGUGGUUUUGGCUUUCGGCUCACAGUAUUGCACCAGGUACUGUGAAUACUGUGAUCAGUAAGACUAGUGAACCCCUUGACUCCAUGAAGCUCAAGUUUUAGUGGGAAAAACAUUGGUUUGGGUGUCGGAAGAGCUGAGUUUAAUCUCCAGCUCUGUGACUUACAGUGACUAAUUGCGUGACCUUGGACAAGUCACUUAUAUAAAGACUCUAGGCCAGAAUCUCUUCAUACAUACAGCAAGGCUAGUUUUUUUGAGUGUUUUUGUGAGACUGAAAUACGAUGAGAUUUAUGAAUCUACUUUGGUAAGCCAGACCAAUGCUUUGUGGAAGUUAGUCAUUUUCGUUUCUUCGCCACUAACUGUGUAUUCAUCCAUCCUCACGCUACUAACAAAGACAUACCCAAGACUGAGUAAUUUAUAAAGGAAAGAGGUUUAAUUGACUCACAGUUCAACAGGGCUGGGGAGACCUCAGGAAACUUGCAAUCAUGGUAGAAGAGGAAACAAACACAUCCUUCUUCACAUGAUGACAAGAAGGAGAAGAAUGUGUGCCAGCAAAGGGGGAAGCCCUUAUAAAACCAUCAGCUCUCAUGAGAACUCACUCACUAUCGCGAGAACAGCAUGAGGGUAACCGCCCCCAUGAUUAAAUCACCUCCAACCAGGUCUCACCCCUGUUGGCGACACAGAGCCAAAUGAUAUCAAACUGUUAUGAUUAUAUUCACCUGCAUGUAACUGACAUGUGACUUCAGUGUUUAGACAAUGGGGACAUCUUCUCAUAUAGCAGGUAGUCUGGAGUUGGGCUUUCCAAGGCUUGAGCAGCUGCUCAGGGAAUUAUUCCCUCUCCUACUCUACCAUCCUUAGUAUGGAACUUUCUUCCUUAUGAUAAAAUGAUGCCUGUUCCAGGAGGGAUAAUGGGAAGAGCCGGGCAAAAGGCAUGUAGAUGGAGUAAAUCCUUUUUGUCAUAGAAACACUAGCUUUCUUAGAAACAUCUCACGAUAAAGUUCUAGUAUUUCUUCUCUGCCAGACACUGACACUUGGCCUCAACUAACUUCAAGGGAGUCUGGGGAAGUGAGUUUUUAACAAGGUGUACUGCUACCCCAAACAAACUCGGGACUCUGUAAGUAAGAAAGAAAAUGAACUGGAUAUUGACAUGGGAGGCAACUAGCUUGACUAUUUUUAUGUUACAGUAAGAUCUUCUUGAGUUUUGUAAACUCCUGGAAGGUAUGCGCCAUGUCGUGUGCAGUUUACUCAUCCAGUGGCAUAGAGCUUUAUUAUCUAUACCAAGCAAACAAUAAAUCAUUGAUUGUAUAUGAAACUGGUCAGUUGCUGAUUCCUUUUUAUAUGACCUCUCAUUAUAAAAAAUACUAUGUGGGCUGAGGCAUGGGGGCUCACACCUGUAAUCCCAGCACUUAGGGAGGCCAAGGUGGGAGAAUUGCUUGAGGCCAGGACAAGACCAGCCUGGGCUACAUAAUGAGAUGUCUGUACAAAAAACAAAAAAUCAAAAGAUUAGUCGGGCAUGAUGGCAUGCGACUCGAGUCCCAGCUACGUGGAAGGCCAAAGCAGGAAGAUUGCUCGACUCCAAGAGGUAGAGGCUGCAGUGAGCCAUGAUUGUGCCACUGUAUUCUAGCCUGGGUGAUAGAGCAAGAACCUGUCUCAAAAAAAAAAAAAGUAUACACACACACACACACACACACACACACACACACACACACCCUCUAGCAUAUGUCACGGGGAUAUUCUGAACAUUAGUUAUUAACUUUGAAGGAAUUGAGAAGGCAUUUAUAACUUCACAGUGCUGGAAUAGGUGCUGUUACUGUCAAUAGUGUUGUUAGUAUCAAAGCUGGCAUUCAUGGAGCAAUUUUAUCUCAACUUCUUAUGCAGUUCAGACCCAUGAAGCCACAAAUGAAGAAAAAUAUGGCCCAGAUGGAAAAGAGAAGACCCACUGAGGGGUUUUUGGAAACCUCAGAGGAUGACUGAAUCCCAUCCCAGAUCUGAUUCUCCCUCCUUCAAGCCCACAUCGCUCCUGCACUUGGAUAGUCCUGGCCUUAGUGAGGCCGUGGCCCAGACACAACCAGACCAUGGGCCUCCCCUGUGGAGAGAUGGCAUUUGGCUGCUUUUCAGAUGUGAAACUCUUUAAGUUUCUGCCAGUGACCCACAUCAUUAACUUUCGGUACAAGUCACCAGUUGGUGAAUGAAAGGACACAAAUCUCUUUCACUGCACCUUUGUAGGGAUUUUUAGAGUCAACAGGAGUGGGAUCUGUCCUUGGCCUGGAAAGCCUUUUGGCCAUUCCCGAGGUGCCAGAGAACCAGCCCCUUACAAGUUAAGAAAUGGAAGUAUAUUUGAAGAAGGACUGAGGAUGACUUGGUUCAUAGGAACCCUCUUCAUAAAUCAAACUCAGAAGACAGCUCUGUAGGAAAAGGAGACUGGAAGAAGAAAAAUAAGUAUUUCUGGCAGAACUUCCGAAAGAACCAGAAAGGAAUAAUGAGACAGACUUCAAAAGGAGAAGACGUUGGUUAUGUUGCCAGUGAAAUAACGAUGAGCGAUGAGGAGCGGAUUCAGCUAAUGAUGAUGGUCAAAGAAAAGAUGAUCACAAUUGAGGAAGCACUUGCUAGGCUCAAGGAAUACGAGGCCCAGCACCGGCAGUCGGCUGCCCUGGACCCUGCUGACUGGCCAGAUGGUUCUUACCCAACGUUUGAUGGCUCAUCAAACUGCAAUUCAAGAGAACAAUCGGAUGAUGAGACUGAGGAGUCGGUGAAGUUUAAGAGGUUACACAAGCUGGUAAACUCCACUCGCAGAGUCAGAAAGAAACUAAUUAGGGUGGAAGAAAUGAAAAAACCCAGCACUGAAGGUGGGGAGGAGCACGUGUUUGAGAAUUCGCCGGUCCUGGAUGAACGGUCCGCCCUCUACUCUGGCGUGCACAAGAAGCCCCUUUUCUUUGAUGGCUCUCCUGAGAAACCUCCCGAAGAUGACUCAGACUCUCUCACCACGUCUCCAUCCUCCAGCAGCCUGGACACCUGGGGGGCUGGCCGGAAGUUGGUCAAAACCUUCAGCAAAGGAGAGAGCCGGGGCCUGAUUAAGCCCCCCAAGAAGAUGGGGACAUUCUUCUCCUACCCAGAAGAAGAAAAGGCCCAGAAAGUGUCCCGCUCCCUCACCGAGGGGGAGAUGAAGAAGGGUCUCGGGUCCCUAAGCCACGGGGUAAGUACGGAUGGUGUUUGCUUCUAUGACAACCACCGUCGCAGGCACCACCUUCUGGUGUCCCUGGAGGAGUUUCAGAGUGUCCGGAAGCAAAUCCGCUUGAAGAAAACGGAUACUAAUUAUUCCUGUUCCAGAGCUUUUCUCUGCCAGCGUCCCUCCAGAAAAGGCGUCACCAGCACCACCUGUGACCUGCAGCUGCUCCGGCAGAAAGGCAAAGGGGGCGGGAGCUGCGGCUUCCCCGGCAGGAGGGUGCGCGGGCGCACCUCGGUCAGCGAGUUCAAUAUCACCUACGUGGUGGAGCGGAGCCUGUACAGCCACCUGAACCUGACCCAGCUAGUGCGGCCUGCCUCAGACAGGACCCUGAGCAAGGCUGAGAGACAGGACCUGAGGCGGUGCCUGCUGGAGGAGGAUGAGGAGGCAAAGAGGAAGUGGGCCGCCACGGUCGACCGCUGUACUAAAAGGGUUCUCUUGAGAAUCCACCAGAAGUCUAGAACCUGCAGUUUUGGAGGAUUUGACUUGACGAAUCGCUCUCUGCACGUUGGCAGUAAUAAUUCUGACCCAAUGGGUAAAGAAGGAGACUUUGUGUACAAAGAAGUCAUCAAAUCACCUACUGCCUCUCGCAUCUCUCUUGGGAAAAAGGUGAAAUCAGUGAAAGAGACGAUGAGAAAGAGAAUGUCUAAAAAAUACAGCAGCUCUGUCUCUGAGCAGGACUCGGGCCUUGAUGGAAUGCCUGGCUCCCCUCCGCCUUCACAGCCCGACCCCGAACACUUGGACAAGCCCAAGCUCAAGGCCGGGGGUUCUGUAGAAAGUCUUCGCAGUUCUCUCAGUGGGCAGAGCUCCAUGAGCGGUCAAACAGUGAGCACCACUGAUUCCUCAACCAGCAACCGGGAAAGCGUCAAGUCGGAAGAUGGGGAUGACGAAGAGCCGCCUUACCGAGGCCCGUUCUGCGGGCGUGCCAGGGUGCACACCGACUUCACCCCCAGUCCCUAUGACACAGACUCACUCAAGCUCAAGAAAGGAGAUAUCAUCGAUAUAAUCAGCAAGCCACCCAUGGGGACCUGGAUGGGCCUGCUGAACAACAAAGUCGGCACGUUCAAGUUCAUCUACGUGGACGUGCUCAGUGAAGACGAGGAGAAACCCAAACGCCCCACCAGGAGGCGUCGGAAAGGACGACCACCCCAGCCCAAGUCUGUGGAGGAUCUCCUGGAUCGGAUUAACCUAAAAGAGCACAUGCCCACUUUCCUGUUCAAUGGAUAUGAAGAUUUGGACACCUUUAAGCUGCUGGAGGAGGAAGACUUGGAUGAGUUAAAUAUCAGGGACCCGGAACACAGAGCUGUUCUCUUGACAGCAGUGGAGCUGUUACAAGAGUAUGACAGUAACAGCGACCAGUCAGGAUCCCAGGAGAAGCUGCUCGUUGACAGCCAGGGCCUGAGUGGAUGCUCACCCCGAGACUCAGGAUGCUACGAAAGCAGUGAGAACCUGGAAAACGGCAAGACUCGGAAAGCUAGCCUCCUAUCUGCCAAGUCAUCCACCGAGCCCAGCUUGAAGUCUUUUAGCAGAAACCAGUUGGGCAAUUACCCAACAUUGCCUUUAAUGAAAUCAGGGGAUGCACUGAAGCAGGGACAGGAGGAGGGCAGGCUGGGUGGUGGCCUUGCCCCAGACACGUCCAAGAGCUGUGACCCACCUGGUGUGACUGGUUUGAAUAAAAACCGAAGAAGCCUCCCAGUUUCCAUCUGCCGGAGCUGUGAGACCCUGGAGGGCCCCCAGACUGUGGACACUUGGCCCCGAUCCCAUUCCCUGGAUGACCUUCAAGUGGAGCCUGGUGCUGAGCAAGACGUGCCUACCGAGGUGACAGAACCGCCCCCUCAGAUUGUACCUGAAGUGCCACAGAAGACGACCGCCUCUUCCACGAAGGCCCAGCCCCUGGAGCAAGACUCUGCUGUCGACAAUGCAUUGCUACUGACCCAAAGCAAGAGAUUUUCUGAACCUCAGAAAUUGACAACUAAGAAACUGGAGGGCUCAAUCGCAGCCUCUGGUCGCGGCCUGUCACCCCCUCAGUGUUUGCCCAGAAACUAUGAUGCUCAGCCUCCUGGAGCUAAACACGGUUUAGCAAGGACGCCUCUGGAGGGCCACAGAAAAGGACACGAGUUUGAAGGAACACACCAUCCCCUGGGCACCAAAGAAGGGGUAGAUGCUGAGCAGAGAAUGCAGCCCAAAAUUCCAUCACAGCCUCCACCUGUUCCUGCCAAAAAGAGCAGAGAACGCCUUGCUAACGGACUCCACCCUGUUCCCAUGGGCCCCAGUGGGGCCCUCCCCAGUCCCGAUGCGCCAUGCCUGCCAGUGAAAAGGGGCAGCCCCGCCAGCCCCACCAGCCCUAGCGACUGUCCCCCAGCACUGGCUCCCAGGCCUCUCUCAGGGCAGGCGCCUGGCAGCCCACCAAGCACAAGGCCGCCCCCCUGGCUCUCAGAGCUCCCCGAGAACACAAGCCUCCAGGAGCACGGUGUGAAGCUGGGCCCGGCUUUGACCAGGAAGGUCUCCUGUGCCCGGGGAGUGGAUCUAGAAACGCUCACUGAAAACAAGCUGCACGCUGAAGGCAUCGAUCUCACGGAGGAGCCGUAUUCUGAUAAGCAUGGCCGCUGUGGGAUUCCUGAAGCCCUGGUGCAGAGAUACGCAGAGGACUUGGAUCAGCCCGAGCGGGACGUCGCCGCCAACAUGGACCAGAUCCGGGUGAAGCAGCUUCGGAAGCAGCACCGCAUGGCGAUUCCAAGUGGUGGACUCACGGAAAUCUGCCGAAAGCCCGUCUCUCCUGGGUGCAUUUCGUCUGUGUCAGAUUGGCUCAUUUCCAUCGGUCUGCCCAUGUACGCCGGCACCCUCUCCACCGCGGGCUUCAGCACACUGAGCCAAGUGCCUUCUCUGUCUCACACUUGCCUUCAGGAGGCCGGCAUCACAGAGGAGAGACACAUAAGAAAGCUCCUAUCUGCAGCCAGACUCUUCAAACUGCCGCCAGGCCCUGAGGCCAUGUAGCCAGGCCCGGAAUGGGCCUCUCUGGACAAGAGCCACCCUUUCACUGUGCAUAUGAUGCUGAUGCAAUUCCUCCAUCAUCUCUGGACGUGCAGACCAGAUCCAGAAGAAAGGCCUGGCGUGUGGCCAAACAGCGUGAAACCUUGGCACAGGACUGAGGAUCCUCUCCUCCAGAAAAGCCCCCUCGAGGAAAUAAAUUAGUGCGGUUCUCUUUGACCCCCAAAGACAAGACAAGCACUUAUUUUUAUUUUCAGAAGACAAAAGAACCAAGAUGCCAACUGGCUGCGAAUGCUCUAUCUCCAGUCUGUCUCUGUGUACUGGUAGAGGCUGGGAGGAGUAGGGGGCAGCCUGUUCCAUUUCUGAUAGUGCCCUUGCUCUUCUGUCUGUCAUCUUGCAGGAUGCCCGAGGGCCAGAUGGGCUUAGCUAGGCCAAAGUAACAGACUCAAGAGUUAUUGUACAUUACUGACCACGCUCAUUUGUUCAAAAGUUAGAACAUCUGGCUGCACCAGGAAAAAAAAAAAAAAAAAGUCCUGUUCUUCUUUAGAUAAACAAGAGACAUUUUCAUAAUUGCUUUCUAGCAAUCAGCUUUUAUUUGCCUUAAUAUAAGCUUUUAAGCAGUUAUCUAACUAGUGUCCACAACCCUGUAACCAUACUUCCACAUCUUCAGCUUAGGCAGACAUCGAACCUCUCUGGGAUGUUUCCAGCAAAAGUGAGCUUUUCUAAUCGUCUCAUUGUAACAUGGCUUAUUUUGUAGAGGUAUUCAUCAGCCACACACUUCAUGUUGGUUUUUGGUUUUUAAGCUAACUACAAAUCUAGUAAAAAGCUAUCUGAAAUUCACAAAUAUCAUGUGUGUGCGUGCGUGCGUGCGCGUGUGUGUCUGUAUUCAUAGUGACUGCUUUUGGUUUUAACCAGUUUAGUAUCGUUACUGUGUGGAUCGUCGCGCUGCAGUAUUGACUUGGAAUCCUGACCAUGUCCAUCCCAAAAUUCAGUCCUCAGUUAACGGAUCAUGUUUGCAAAAGGUCACUGUGAGGCUGCAUAUUUCAGAAAGAUGUCCUUAAUAAGGGAAGUCAUGUAUAAGAUGUUUUCUAAAAGACUUUUCAGUAUUACAACUAAUACUAUUAUUAUCCUUCUUUUUUUAUUUAGAUAAUUCUUUUAAUUUAAACAAAGGUUCACUAUGGAACCAGACAAAUCUCAUUAGCCAUGUGUUAAGUAUUUGCUACUUUAAAUUGUUUUACAACUGAUUUCAGCACAUUCUAUCCUUUUUUUUUUUUGAAAUGGAGUUUCGCUCUUGUCACCCAGGCUGGAGUGCAAUGGCACGAUCUUGGCUCACUGCAACCUCAGUCUCCCAGGUUCAAGUGAUUCUCCUGCCUUAGCCUCCCGAGUAGCUGGGAUUAUAGGCACCCACCACCACGCCCAGCUAAUUUUUGUAUUAUUAGUAGAGACAGGGUUUCACCAUGUUGGCCAGGCUGGUCUCAAACUCAACUCCUGACCUCAGGUGGUCCACCCGCCUCAGCCUCCCAAAGUGCUGGGAUUACAGGUGUGAGCCACCGCACCUGGCCUCUGUCCUCUUUUAGUCUAGUGUCUGGUUUUCUAGCAAACAGUAAAUUUAAACAAGUAAACUAUUAUGGUUUCCAUUGCUUACAAAAUGAUUUUCCUUUACAUUCUUAUCAUGAACACUAUUUUAAGCAUCAAAUGCAAUCAUCUAAAAUAUAAAGGUCAAUCAUUUAUAAUAGAAACACCUUGACCACAAGCCCUUGAUUGAACAUUUUAUAAUAUUUCAUCUACUUAUUAAAACAAAUAAUUUCCCUUGGGUUGGAGGGGAAGUGAUUUCAUAAAUUAAUUAGAAAGCCAUCUUUAGCAUAUUGCUUAUGUCUGGAUCCAUGUUUCUGAGGAAAAAGACAUUCUCAGGUGAUGUAUUUUUUUCAUGCAUUAGUAUGCAUUUUUAAAAAAUAAUGCAUGUUUCUUUAAUAAUUAAUUUUCAUCUUCUAUAAGAUGCCAUGUGAAGAAGUUGUGGAAAUGUAGAAUAAAAAGCUAAAGCUGCCAAAUUUCUGUUGAACUCUUAAAAACAGCUCAUGUUUGUUUGUCCUCUCGGGUUGUGGCCUAGCCUAUUUGCAAUGUAAUGAAGCUGCAGGGUUCUUGUAUAGCUAAAGCGUUCAAUGCAUUUCACGUGCUGUGGUGGAUGUGGGUGCUGUAGACAGGCUUCUUCUCUUCCUGCUCUCAAAAUACCUCGGCUUGACAUUUGGACAGAUCCUGUCAUUGUUUAAGCUGAGCAAAAAACCACACAAAAGUUGUGUAAGAGAUGAGAUAACAAAGGAGCGAGAGAAAUCUCAUGUGAAUUUCCAAGUUUUAAUUCGUUCUCCAUGAAGGAUUUUCAUUUCAGUGAAAGUCGCAGCAGAAGAGGGAACUUUCUGGAGUUUUUGAGAAUGCCAAACCACAUUUUUAUCACACUUCUUUGGAAAUCAAUGCCUUUGCAUAGAAAAUCAAAUUCAGGGACCACAAAGAAUUUUCAGUGGGAAUGUCUAGUCUGAGGGGUCUGAGGUUGUUUUUACUUUAUUGUGUUGUUUAAAUAUUUUAAAAAUAUCUUUAGCGUUUGGUCUUUUUUUUUUCUGUAAACAUUUAAUUUGGUCUGAGAAAAGCUGAAUGUUUGGGUGUGACGUUUGACUGAGGUGGAUUGGGGCUGCCUGUGGACAUUAGUGAACAGGUGGUAGGCUUCAGGAAUAUCCAGUUUUAAUCAGUUGCAUUUGGUACAGAAUUUUGAGUAAUGGUGAAAAUUGUUGUCUUUGGAAAGCACAAAAGAAACCUGGAAAGGCAGUUCGGCUCAGGUAGCUACACAUAACAUUGUGUAUGAUUUUCACUUCAAAGCUGUCUGGAAGGAAAUGCAGUCAGCUCCAGCUAGUACUAUUUAUGUACCCAGAUAACUAAGAUAUUGUUUCAUGGCCUUGCCUUAGUCAGAGGCCCUUUUCUCUGUCCUGAACCCCCAGGUAUGGGUGAAAUUGGAAAUUACUAAUCUAUUGGAAAUCAGUUCCUGACAUAGUAAAGUUUGCUUUCAUAACUGCAGCAAAAAAGGUCAACUUGCCAAGUCACUGCUGCCAUGUGUGUACUGUAUUAUUUUCAGAAAAAAAUAUAAUAGUCUGAGUCCAAGUUAUCUUGAUUUAAAAUUGAUAGAGAAAAGAAACUGUCGAGCAAGUUAUAUAACAACUAACAACAUUGCACUUUCUGUAUAUGAAAUCAAUAUUUAAAUAACUUAUUUUUCUCCAUUGCUGUUCUUAAAAACAUUGUAAGUAGCUGUAAUAUACCAGUACCAAUAUGUUCUUGCAAUUGCUUCAGCCCAAGAAAGCUGUGUAUUGUUUUAAAAAUUGUAAAAAUUAUUGUGAUGAUUCAUUUAGCAUAAAGAGAGGUGGACGGAAGGGUUUUCCUAUGUAUCAAAACUUGUCUAUAAUUAUGUCAUCUAUGUACCUAGAAAAAAGUAAAUAAAUUUCUUCAGUUGAA